GAGUGCCCAGCCGCCCGGCGCCCAGGCCUGGGGCACCGCGAGUGCCGAACCUUCGGCUGGUGAGUGCGCACCCCCUCCCCGGGGUUUCCGCCCCGAUCCCGCCUCCAGCCCGUGCCCCAGAGCUCCAGGUCGCCGACCCGGGCCCUGGGGAGUGACUCAGCGCAAGGAUGGUGGCGACUUGCGGGGGCUGGAGAUUCGAACUGUUCAAGGCCUUGAAUGCUGGGAUGAGUGGGGACACCAAGAUGCCUGGCGAACAGCAGGCAGAGGAAGAGGAGGAGGAAGAGAUGCAGGAGGAGAUGGUGCUGCUGGUGAAGGGUGAGGAGGAUGAGGGUGAGGAGAAGUAUGAGGUGGUGAAACUCAAGAUCCCCAUGGACAACAAGGAGGUCCCGGGCGAGGCGCCCGCGCCGUCCGCCGACCCGGCGCGUCCCCACGCGUGCCCCGACUGCGGCCGCGCCUUCGCGCGCCGCUCCACGCUGGCGAAGCACGCGCGCACGCACACGGGCGAACGGCCCUUCGGGUGCACCGAGUGCGGGCGGCGCUUCUCACAGAAGUCGGCGCUGACCAAACACGGCCGCACGCACACGGGCGAGCGGCCCUACGAGUGCCCCGAGUGCGACAAACGCUUCUCGGCCGCCUCGAACCUGCGGCAGCACCGGCGGCGGCACACGGGCGAGAAGCCGUACGCAUGCGCGCACUGCGGCCGCCGCUUCGCGCAGAGCUCCAACUACGCACAGCACCUGCGCGUGCACACGGGCGAGAAGCCGUACGCGUGCCCGGACUGCGGACGCGCCUUUGGCGGCAGCUCGUGCCUGGCGCGCCACCGACGCACGCACACGGGCGAGCGGCCCUACGCUUGCGCCGACUGCGGCACGCGCUUCGCUCAGAGCUCGGCGCUGGCCAAGCACCGGCGCGUGCACACGGGCGAGAAGCCGCACCGCUGCGCUGUGUGUGGCCGUCGCUUCGGCCACCGCUCCAACCUGGCGGAGCACGCGCGCACGCACACAGGCGAGCGGCCCUACCCCUGCGCCGAGUGCGGCCGCCGCUUCCGCCUAAGCUCGCACUUCAUUCGCCACCGACGCGCGCACAUGCGGCGCCGCCUGUAUAUUUGCGCCGGCUGCGGCAGGGACUUCAAGCUGCCCCCUGGCGCCACGGCCGCCACUGCCACCGAGCGUUGCCCGGAGUGUGAGGGCAGCUGAGUCCCGCAGGGCUGCGGAGGGGCGCGCUGGGGCUUCGACCUGGCUGCACUAACCCAGGCUCCUCCUCGCCCCGGCCUCCGGGUCUGGGAAAUUGAGGGGACGGCAGGCCCGGCUGCCCUGGAACUGGGAGACAGGGAGAAUCCCCUGCCGGGGUCCCUGGAAACAGUGCCCACCCCACAUCACUACAUUCCCUCGGCCCGUGUUAGUGAAUAAAGUAUUAUAUCCUCACCCCACCCGUGCCUGUGAGUGAGGUGGGUGGGAGAGGAAGAAAGUUGGGGUUCUCCAGGCUCAGGUGCCAAGUGAGUUGUCAAGGAACCAAAUGGGGAUGUAAACCUAAAAGGGGUUCCCGGCACCUCGGUUUGUGUUGGUUGGAGGUGAUCGCACACUUGGCCCUUGGUUACGUCCUCAUAACCUUAGACCUGAAAGGGCCCAUAAAUAUACUAUGUUCACGAUCAGACACGCACUGCAUUCGGCAGAGCUCCAGUGAGCAAGGCACGACCCUCAGAUCUCAGUCUAGUGAAGGAGAGAAAACUGUAAUAACACUACGUUAAAGGUUUUAACUGCUUUGUUAUGUAAGCUUACCCAGCCCGGCGCACAGUGACUCACGCCUGUAAUCCCAGCACUUUGGGAGGGCGAGGCUAGCAGAUCACUUGAGGUUAGGAGUUCGAUACCAGCCUGGCCAACAUGGUGAAACCCGGUCUCUACUAAAAAUACAAAAAUUAACUGGGUGUGGUGGCGGGCGCCUGUAAUCCCAGCUACUGAGGGGGCUGAGGCAUGAGAAUCACUUGAACCUGGGAGACAGAGGUUGCAAUGAACCGAGAUAGUGCCAUUGCACUCCGGCCUGGGCAACAGAGGAAGACUGCCUCAAACAAACAAAAAACAACAAACCAAACCAAACCAAACCAAAAAAAUCUCAAAGCGAUUGGACCUAGCAGCUCAUGCCUGUAAUCUCCAGCACUUUGGGAGGCGGAGGCAGGAGGAUCUCUUGAAGUCAAGAGUUUGAGAUCAGCCUGGAGAACAAAGUGAGACCCCCAUCUAUUAAAAAAA